AAAGAGCCCGGGACCAGCGCAGAGGGCCUGAUGCCUGAUCUGUCAAGUCUGUCCGACCGUGCCUGUCUGCUGUCCCCCCAGCUGUUCCAGUGGUGGAUUGGCAGGACCGGGUGCCUACCCGGUACUCCUUACCAAAGGAGCCCCUGGUAGUGCCCACCUAGCCCAGGACAAGGAGUGGAACGGGAGCUGCAGCUGCAGUGGUCACGAAGGCAGCCUGGAGGAGGUGGCCAUGGAGGAUAGCCUUCGUUAUCGUCAGCCUCUGGUGAGAAGCAGCAGCAUCCUUCCAGAGAGUCACUUCUGAUCCCCAAGCCGCAUAACCGCGAAUGAACCAAAGAGAACCCGAAGCCGGUGGGAACUCAGCGCAGUCUCACCCUGCCCCUCGGGAACCGCUUCUCAGCAGCGGCAGCCGAAGUCUGACGACGCUUAGCAACCGUUACCUUGACAACGCAAUCCUAUCGCGCACCAUGGAGUGCGGCGCCCCUCUGCAUCCCAGAAGGCACCGCGCUGUCCCUAAGCCUUCCGCCCCUCUCCGUCCCAACAUGCAACGAGGCUCACAGUCAAUGAAUCGUCAUCAGGUAUGAACGAGGCUCGGCCACCAACUACAUCACCCGGAACAAAGCCCGGAAGAAGCUCCAGCUGAGCUUGGCUGACUUUAGGCGGCUGUGCAUUCUGAAGGGCAUUUAUCCCCAUGAACCCAAACACAAGAAGAAGGUUAACAAGGGUUCUACAGCAGCCCGAACGUUUUACCUUAUCAAAGACAUCAGGUUUCUCCUCCACGAACCCAUUGUCAACAAGUUCCGUGAAUACAAGGUGUUCGUCCGGAAGCUCCGGAAGGCUUAUGGGAAGAGCGAGUGGAACACUGUAGAGCGUUUAAAGGACAAUAAGCCCAACUACAAACUCGACCACAUCAUCAAGGAACGGUAUCCCACGUUCAUCGAUGCCCUGCGGGACCUGGACGAUGCCCUCUCCAUGUGCUUCCUGUUUUCCACCUUCCCGCGGACUGGCAAGUGCCACGUGCAGACCAUUCAGCUGUGCCGCCGGCUCACUGUGGAGUUCAUGCACUACAUUAUCGCUGCCCGUGCCCUGCGCAAGGUCUUCCUGUCCAUCAAAGGCAUUUACUACCAGGCCGAGGUACUGGGGCAGCCCAUCGUGUGGAUCACUCCCUAUGCCUUCUCCCAUGACCACCCGACAGACGUGGACUACAGGGUCAUGGCCACCUUCACCGAGUUCUACACCACGCUGCUGGGCUUUGUCAACUUCCGCCUUUACCAGUUGCUCAACCUCCACUAUCCCCCGAAGCUCGAGGGUCAGGCCCAAGCAGAGGCAAAGGCCGGUGAGGGCACCUACGCGUUGGACUCCGAGAGUUGUAUGGAGAAACUGGCAGCCCUCAGUGCCAGCCUGGCCCGCGUGGUGGUGCCUGCCACAGAGGAGGAGGCCGAGGUGGAUGAGUUUCCCACCGAUGGGGAGAUGUCAGCGCAGGAGGAAGACCGCAGGAAGGAGCUGGAGGCGCAGGAGAAGCACAAGAAGCUUUUUGAGGGCCUGAAGUUCUUCCUGAACCGAGAGGUGCCCCGUGAGGCCCUGGCCUUCAUCAUCAGGAGUUUUGGUGGGGAAGUGUCCUGGGACAAAUCUUUGUGCAUUGGGGCCACCUAUGACGUCACAGACUCCCGCAUCACCCAUCAGAUUGUCGACCGGCCUGGGCAGCAGACCUCAGUCAUUGGCAGGUGCUACGUGCAGCCCCAGUGGGUGUUUGACUCAGUGAACGCCAGGCUCCUUCUCCCCGUGGCAGAGUACUUCUCUGGGGUGCAGCUGCCCCCACACCUUUCACCCUUUGUGACCGAGAAGGAAGGAGAUUACGUUCCACCUGAGAAGCUGAAGCUGCUGGCUCUGCAGCGGGGAGAGGACCCAGGAAACCUGAAUGAGUCAGAAGAGGAGGAGGAAGAGGACGACAACAACGAAGGUGAUGGUGAUGAAGAGGGAGAAAAUGAGGAGGAGGAGGAAGAUGCAGAGGCUGGUUCAGAAAAGGAGGAAGAGGCCCGGCUGGCAGCCCUGGAAGAGCAGAGGAUGGAGGGGAAGAAGCCCAGGGUGAUGGCAGGCACCUUGAAGCUGGAGGAUAAGCAGCGGCUGGCCCAGGAGGAGGAGAGUGAGGCCAAGCGCCUGGCCAUUAUGAUGAUGAAGAAGCGGGAGAAGUACCUGUACCAGAAGAUCAUGUUUGGCAAGAGGCGAAAAAUCCGAGAGGCCAACAAGCUGGCGGAGAAGCGGAAAGCCCACGAUGAGGCGGUGAGGUCUGAGAAGAAGGCCAAGAAGGCAAGGCCGGAGUGAGUGCCUGCGGCCCCUCACAGGGCUGAGGCCAGCCCCUAGCAGCUGGAUGUGGCAGAGGCAGGCCAGAGGACCUAAGUGUGAUGGACCAGAGUCACUUCUCCUCCUCCUUUCUCCAGCCAGCCCUGACCCCUCAUGCUCUCUGGCUGGGCCAGUGGGCAGCCCUCGCUUCCCUUGGAUGGAGCUGCCCUGCUGGUGCCUGGUCAGAGAAGAGGCCUCUGUGCCCAGCCUGAUUCUCUGCUCCCAGGAGCCAGUGACAUGAGGUGCAGAGGCCCACCCAGCCCCCUACCUACUGCCCCCAUUCAUCCUGGCUUUCCACAGCCCCCUCCCACACAGUUGGACCCGUGAUUCUCAGGGUGCUGUGAUGGGGUGAGGGUAGGGGGAGCAUUUGUUAUUAAAUGACUGGACUUUUGUGCCAAUUGCA